AGUACAAAACUAGUAGUGAGAAAGGAAGCUGGGAAGAGACUGGGAAGAGGCAACCGACCUCAUUAACAAAAGCUCAGUUUUGUCCCUGCGGACCCAACCAGCAGAAGGCACGGGGCUAGCGGUGGCUGUCCGCCAGGGAGGUCGGGCUCUGUGUAAACAGUAGAAGGCAUCUUUAUCAUGCCCUUCUCACAGGGAGUCCUGAGGCUUGGCGCUCAGGAAGUUUGCAAAGCUGCAGCAGCUGCCUUGGAGAAGACCAGCAAAGAAAGUGGAGUGUGUAUGUGAACUUCAAUUCUGUAUUUUCUGUGAGGUGGGUUAAUGGAUUUUUAGUAAAAAGAAAUCUCAAACACAGCUGACCUGAAAGACUGGAAUUUCAGCUCUCUUCCUUCCCGGGGUUCUUUUUCCUCCCCCUUCCUCUCAAAGCCCUUUAAACCAGAUUGCUGUGUCAGUGACUCUUAUCCUGCCCGCCAGUUCCAAGGGUUUCUAACUUUUUGUCUUGGAAAGGAAAACCACUACCUGAUUAGAAAAGCACUUGGGAAGCCCAUUAAUCUUGCCGGCGUUGUCAGGAGUGAUCAGCGAGUUUUAUUAAAAGCCCUGGGAUUGCCUGAAAGGCCCCCUUGUCUGACUUUGAAAUGAAAGGGGCAUGUUAAGAUCUCGGGGCACAUUGUCAGGACCCCUCACCCUGCCCCUUGGACUAUGAGCUGACCCUCCAGGAGGAAGCACAGAAGCCCUCCUUUGUUAAAGGGAUUUCGCCGGUGGACAGAGAAGAGUUGGGCCCUGUCAGCAUGAACUCUCUGAGUUGGGGGGCUGCGAAUGCCGUGCUGCUGCUGCUCCUCCUGGCCUGGGCCAGCCCCACCUUCAUCAGCAUCAACCGCGGGGUGAGGGUGAUGAAGGGCCACUCUGCCUUCCUGUCAGGAGAUGACCUGAAGUUUGCCAUCCCUAAAGAGAAAGAUGCCUGCAAAGUGGAAGUUGUGAUGAAUGAGCCAAUAACCCAGAGGGUUGGGAAACUCACUCCACAGGUCUUUGACUGCCAUUUCCUUCCCAACGAAGUCAAGUAUGUUCACAAUGGUUGUCCAAUUCUUGAUGAAGACACAGUGAAGCUCAGACUUUACAGAUUUACUGAAAGAGAUACCUUCAUAGAAACUUUUAUCCUGUGGGUCUAUCUCCUGGAACCAGACUGUAACAUCAUCCAUAUGAGUAACAAUGUGCUGGAGGUGCCUGAAUUCAAUGGCUUGUCCCAAGCGAUUGAUAAAAAUCUGCUCAGAUUCGAUUAUGAUAGGAUGGCUAGCCUGGAAUGUACCGUCAGCCUGGACACUGCGAGAACUCGGCUGCCAGCCCAUGGCCAGAUGGUUCUCGGGGAGCCUCGACCAGAAGAACCUCGUGGAGAUCAGCCACACAGUUUUUUCCCAGAGUCCCGUAUGAUGUCUUUUAAUGCCUUUCUGGAACUGAGAGCAAAACUGAAGUGUCCAGGUGGGAGCUGUACCCCAGGAUUAAAGAAAAUAGGAAGCCUCAAAGUGAGCUGUGAGGAGUUCCUGCUGAUGGGCCUUCGUUAUCAGCAUCUGGAUCCCCCUUCACCCAACAUUGAUUAUAUCUCCAUCCAACUGGACCUCACAGAUACCAGGAGCAAAAUUGUGUACAAGUCAGAGAGUGCGUGGCUGCCUGUCUAUAUCAGAGCUGGAAUUCCGAAUCAGAUUCCAAAGGCUGCAUUCAUGGCCGUGUUUAUUCUGGAAGUGGAUCAGUUCAUCCUGACCUCCUUGACUACAUCAGUUCUGGACUGUGAAGAAGAUGAGACCCCUAAACCCUUGCUGGUGUUCAACAUUACUAAAGCCCCGCUCCAGGGCUAUGUGACUCACCUGUUGGAUCACACCAGACCAAUCUCCUCAUUCACCUGGAAAGAUCUCAGUGACAUGCAGAUCGCCUAUCAGCCACCAAACAGCAGCCAUUCUGAGAGGAGACAUGAUGAGGUAGAAUUGGAGGUAUACGACUUCUUCUUUGAAAGGAGUGCACCUAUGACAGUCCACAUCUCCAUCAGAACAGCAGAUACAAAUGCCCCCCGUGUAUCCUGGAAUACAGGUCUGAGUCUCCUUGAGGGGCAGUCUCGAGCCAUCACUUGGGAACAGUUUCAGGUUGUCGACAAUGACGACAUUGGUGCUGUCCGGCUAGUCACCGUUGGUGGCCUGCAGCAUGGAUGGCUGACUUUAAGAGGGGGGAAAGGGUUUCUCUUCACCGUGGCUGACCUCCAGGCUGGAGUUGUUCGCUAUCAUCAUGAUGACAGCGACUCCACCAAAGACUUCGUGGUCUUCCGGAUAUUUGAUGGCCAUCACAGCAUCCGUCACAAAUUCCCCAUCAACGUCUUGCCCAAAGAUGAUAGUCCCCCGUUCCUCAUAACCAAUGUUGUGAUUGAACUGGAGGAGGGGCAGACCAUCCUGAUCCAGGGAUCCAUGCUGCGAGCUUCAGAUGUGGACGCCAGUGAUGACUACAUCUUCUUCAAUAUCACAAAGCCUCCACAGGCUGGGGAGAUCAUGAAGAAGCCAGGGCCAGGACUGAUAGGCUAUCCUGUCCAUGGCUUCCUUCAGAGGGAUUUGUUUAAUGGAAUCAUUUAUUAUCGUCAUUUUGGUGGAGAAAUCUUUGAAGAUUCUUUUCAAUUUGUCCUGUGGGACAGCCAUGAACCUCCAAAUCUUUCAGUGCCACAGGUGGCAACAAUCCAUAUAACUCCAGUGGAUGACCAGCUUCCAAAAGAGGCUCCUGGAGUUUCUCGGCAUUUGGUUGUCAAGGAAACUGAGGUGGCCUAUAUAACUAAGAAACAGCUACAUUUUAUAGAUUCAGAAUCAUAUGACAGGGAGCUGGUCUACACAAUAACUACUCCUCCAUUUUUCUCCUUCAGCCACAGACACUUGGAUGCUGGGAAAUUAUUUAUGGUGGACAGCAUACCAAAAGUAGUUAAGAAUCCUACGGCCCUGGAGCUGAGGUCAUUCACUCAGCAUGCUGUGAACUAUAUGAAAGUGGCCUACAUGCCCCCCAUGCAAGACAUUGGUCCCCAUUGCAGAGAUGUCCAGUUCACAUUUUCUGUCAGUAACCAACAUGGCGGUACUUUGCAUGGGAUCUGCUUUAACAUUACAAUCCUCCCAGUGGACAAUCAAGUUCCUGAGGCGUUCACCAACCCUCUGAAAGUGACUGAGGGAGGUCAAAGCAUCAUCAGCACAGAGCACAUUCUAAUUUCUGAUGCAGAUACCAAGCUGGACAAUAUUGACCUCUCCCUGCGGGAAUUGCCUCUGCACGGAAGGGUGGAGCUGAAUGGAUUUCCUCUAAAUUCAGGGGGCACAUUUUCUUGGGGCGAUCUCCAUACCUUAAAAGUUAGGUAUCAACAUGAUGGAACUGAAGUUCUUCAGGAUGACCUACUCUUGGAGGUCACCGAUGGCACAAAUUCAGCAGAAUUUGUACUACAUGUUGAGGUAUUCCCUGUCAACGAUGAGCCACCAGUCUUAAAGGCUGACCUCAUGCCUGUCAUGAAUUGCUCAGAGGGAGGAGAGGUGGUCAUCACCUCUGAAUACAUUUUUGCUACUGAUGUGGACAGCGAUAACUUGAAGUUGAUGUUUGUGAUUGCUCGCGAACCUCAGCAUGGGGUGGUGAGGAGAGCUGGAGUCACAGUGGAUCAGUUCUCUCAGAGAGAUGUUAUCUCAGAGGCCGUGACAUACAAACACACAGGUGGCGAGAUUGGCCUGAUGCCUUGUUUUGACACCAUUACAUUGGUGGUUUCGGAUGGAGAGGCUGGCCCUUUUGUGAAUGGCUGUUGCUACAAUGGACCCAAUCCAUCUGUUCCACUUCAUGCGUCCUUUCCAGUGUAUGAUCUCAACAUCACGGUAUACCCAGUAGACAACCAGCCACCUUCCAUUGCAAUAGGUCCCGUGUUUGUUGUAGAUGAGGGCUGCUCAACAGCCCUUACUGUUAACCAUUUGUCCGCCACUGACCCUGACACUGCAGCAGAUGACUUGGAAUUUGUUUUGGUUUCUCCUCCUCAGUUUGGCUACCUCGAAAAUAUACUCCCUUCUGUGGGUUUUGAAAAAAGCAAUAUUGGCAUAAGUAUAGAUUCAUUUCAGUGGAAAGACAUGAACGCUUUUCACAUUAACUAUGUGCAGUCCAGGCAUCUGAGGAUAGAACCAACUGCCGACCAGUUCACGGUGUACGUCACAGAUGGGAAGCAUCACUCCUUGGAGAUACCAUUUUCUAUUAUAAUCAACCCCACAAAUGAUGAAGCUCCUGACUUUGUAGUGCAGAAUAUUACUGUGUGUGAGGGUCAGAUGAAAGAGCUGGACUCUUCCAUCAUCAGCGCUGUGGACCUGGACAUUCCCCAGGAUGCCCUGCUGUUCAGCAUCACUCAAAAGCCACGCCAUGGCCUCCUCAUCGAUAGGGGGUUUAGCAAAGACUUCUCUGAGAAUAAGCAGCCAGCCAACCCUCACCAGAAACAUGCACCUGUUCACAGCUUUUCCAUGGAACUCCUCAAGACUGGAAUGAGGUUGACGUACAUGCAUGAUGACUCAGAGAGCCUUGCUGAUGAUUUUACAAUCCAAUUGUCAGAUGGGAAACAUAAGAUACUUAAAACCAUUUCAGUAGAGGUCAUCCCAGUUAAUGAUGAAAAACCAAUGCUGAGCAAGAAGGCUGAAAUUGCAAUGAAUAUGGGUGAAACUCGUAUUAUUUCCAGUGCUAUUCUUUCAGCCAUAGAUGAAGACUCACCCAGGGAGAAGAUUUACUAUGUAUUUGAAAGGCUUCCCCAAAAUGGGCAACUUCAGCUUAAGAUAGGGAGGGACUGGGUUCCUCUCUCCCCUGGCAUGAAAUGCACUCAGGAGGAAGUGGAUCUGAACUUGCUGAGAUACACACACACCGGGGCAAUGGAUUCCCAGAAUCAAGAUAGCUUCACCUUCUACCUUUGGGAUGGCAACAACAGGUCCCCUGCUCUUGACUGUCAAAUCACCAUCAAGGACAUGGAAAAAGGUGAUAUUGUCAUCCUUACAAAACCACUCGUGGUGUCUAAAGGUGAUAGAGGUUUCUUAACAACCACCACGCUCCUGGCUGUGGACGGAACAGACAAGCCUGAGGAACUGCUCUAUGUCAUCACCUCCCCUCCGCGAUAUGGCCAGAUCGAAUAUGUUCACUAUCCUGGAGUUCCCAUUACAAACUUCAGCCAAAUGGAUGUAGUGGGGCAGACAGUUUGCUAUGUACACAAGAGCAAGGUGACUGUCUCCAGUGACAGAUUCAGAUUCAUCAUCAGCAAUGGACUGCGGACCGAGCACGGGGUGUUUGAGAUCACACUGGAGACUGUGGACAGAGCCCUGCCUGUGGUAACCAGGAACAAGGGGUUGAGACUGGCCCAAGGGGCCGUGGGCCUGCUUUCCCCUGACCUCCUUCAGCUGACCGACCCUGAUACACCUGCGGAGAACCUCACCUUCCUCUUGGUUCAGCUCCCCCAGCAUGGCCAGCUCUACCUGUGGGGGACAGGGCUACUUCAACACAAUUUCACCCAGCAGGAUGUGGACAGCAAGAAUGUGGCCUAUCGGCACUCAGGAGGGGACUCCCAGACUGACUGCUUUACUUUCAUGGCCACAGAUGGGACAAACCAAGGCUUUAUUGUGAAUGGGAGAGUGUGGGAAGAACCUGUUUUAUUCACCAUUCAGGUAGACCAAUUGGACAAAACAGCUCCUCGUAUCACACUCUUGCAUUCCCCUUCUCAAGUGGGGCUCCUGAAAAAUGGCUGCUACGGGAUUUACAUCACUUCCCGCGUGUUGAAGGCAUCAGACCCUGACACUGAGGACGAUCAGAUCAUCUUUAAAAUUCUACAAGGCCCAAAACAUGGACAUCUGGAGAACACAACAACAGGUGAAUUUAUCCAUGAGAAAUUUAGCCAAAAGGACUUAAACAGUAAGACUAUUCUUUACAUCAUAAACCCAUCUUUGGAAGUAAAUUCAGAUACCGUGGAAUUUCAAAUCAUGGACCCCACAGGGAACUCGGCCACUCCUCAAAUUUUGGAACUGAAGUGGUCUCAUAUUGAAUGGUCACAGACCGAAUAUGAAGUCUGUGAGAAUGUGGGUUUGUUGCCCUUGGAAAUUAUCAGAAGGGGAUAUUCCAUGGACUCGGCCUUUGUGGGUAUAAAGGUCAACCAAGUGUCAGCUGCAGUUGGAAAAGAUUUCACCGUGAUUCCAUCUAAACUGAUUCAGUUUGACCCAGCUUCCAUGAUUGGGUGAAGAAACAGAGUGAAAAACCGAAGACAGUGGGAUGCCGUAAGGUUUGAGAACUCUUACGUGGGAGCUGGAAGGAAGCUUGCCUUGAAGUUGCAACUAUGCUACCAAACCAAAAAAAUACCAAACAAACAAAAGCAAACCCUAACUACUUUGCAUUCAGCUAUUGUGACUAGUCUUGAGUGGAUAUAAAAAUACUCCUAAGAAAAUGAUUGUUUUCCUUUAAAAUAUGCAUUAUUGAAAGGCUUGCAGCAUUCUUAAUUGAUCAUCAUUCCUUAGAGUCAAAAUGUUUUCCAAGGGAACAGAUCUCUAAUGUGGCAUUUACUAAAAAAUAUUGAGAAAAUGUCUUUCAAUAGAGAAAUCUGCUUUGCAGGAAAACAUCCAGGAACUCACCUACUCUGUAAAGUGGAAUAUGUCUGCAUAAAAUGACACCUCUGUUUUCUCUUCAGCACCUUUUGUUUUGUGGGAACAGGGAGCCAGUCCAAGCCUUCUGAAAAUGCUUGUAUAUCUCAGGGACUUAGCAAAUACUUUGCACCUUGAAAGUGAAAGAGGAAGGGAAAAAAUGAUAAAGUUUUGACUUCCAAUCUCAUUAACCUAAAGAGUUAGUCCUCUGUGCACACCUGGAAGGCAUAGAAACCAAGUUGGAAUGCACACAAACAAAUCAGAAGCACUUAAAUGAAACUCAAAAGAUAUUUUCUCCAACCCCUAACCAUCUGGUUCUACUCCGUAAGGUCCAACAAAAACCUUAAGUUUUUUGUUUUUUGUUUGUUUGUUUGUUUGUUUGGGGGGUACUAUAAUUUUAAAAAAUUAACCUUAAAAUCAGAGAGUCGGUUGGGAGUUGGAAAUAUUUUCUGUAUUGGAUUUUAUUUACAUGAUGCUUAACUUUAUGGUCUUUGAGGGUCAAAACAGUUCUCCAAGUACUAAUAAUCAUAUUAUUCAUAUGCUUUCUUCAUUGACCACCUCUUAUCUUUUCAUGCCAAUUGUAUUACAGCAGCUGUCUAUGUGGUCUUCAAACUUCUAGCCUAUCUGUCUAUCUGCCUGGAUCUCCAGACUUUCUCACAUAACACUCUCAGGUUCAUUUUGCUAAUCCACUUUCAGUGUGUGACUUCUUUGUUCAAGACCCUUCCCUCUUGCCUAUGUUGUAAAGUCUGAAUCUGGCCAGGUGCCCAGGGCUCUCUGCAGUCUGGCUACAAAUAAUCUUUGCAGCCUUAUGGCCUCCUGUCCACCCAUGUAACCUCUCUAUUCCAGCCAGCUAAUUCACUCACCCUUCCCGAGUCAAGACCUCUGCUUUGCUAUCUUCCUGUCUUUACUUAUGUUGUUUUCCUGUUUCCUCCCUCCUAAUCCUUUCACUUCUAAAGCCCACAUUUAUAUAGGCUCUACAAUCUAUUCUGUAUCUUUUAGUAGGUAAACAUACAUAGCUUUCAAUAAUUAUUUGACUUUUCUGGUUUUGCUUCUGUCUCCCCCAAAAGAUUUUAAGCUCCCUUAGAUCAGGGCUUGGCUUAUGUUACACCUCUGGUAUUCUCCAUAGCAUCUAAUGCAAAGAUAAGCAUAUCAUAAGUACAAAAUAUAUAUUUUGAUGUAUUGAUUUAUCCAUCCAUGAGAUGGGAAUUGUAUGGUAUUAUUAUACAUACUAGAUGCUUCAACUUCUGCUUUUGCAAAGACUGUGAACGUAAUUGGUUUAAAAACUCAGUACUGGAAGCUUAAUAAAUUAGCUGUCAGCCUGUUUUUGAAUAAAAUCUAUUUAUUCCAAGUACACCUAAUUUUUUCCCCUCUAAGUGCAGCCAGCCAAAAGUAGAAGAAGUGGAUAGCUUCACCUUUCCAUUGACUUCUGUUGAGGAUUGAAGAGACUGAUUAGAUCAUGAGAUCUAUGUGAGGCAUACCUUCAAGAAAGAGGCCACCAUAUAGAUGGACAGUUGAGAGGUAUAAGUCUGUAGAAGGCAAUCUGCAAGAUAAAAGAGUCGUUUUUUGGAGAUGGGGACAAGGUCUCACUCUGUUGCCCAGGCUGGAGUGCAGUGACACAUCCUGGGCUCACUGCAGCCUUGACCUUCUGGGCUCAAGCGAUCCUCCCACCUCAGCCUCCUGAGUGGUUGAGAUCACAGGCACGUGCCACCACGCCCACCUAAUUUUUGUUUUUGUUUUUGUUUUAUUGUAGAGAUGGGGUUUUGCUCUGUUGGCCAGGUUGGUCUCAAACUCCUGAGCUCAAGUGAUCUGCCCGCCUUGGCCUGCCAAAGUGCUGGGAUUACAGUUGUUUACCACUGCACCCGGCCAAGAGUUACAUUUUUAAGAGAAGACUUUUUAAAAAGUUUAACUGUAUCAUAUAGAGGGGCUUAAAGGAGUAAAAGCACUCAAAUAGCCAAUGAGCAAAUGGCAGAGUAAGCUUUUCCAUCUCAGCUAAGAAAAGUUAAAUCGAUAAGUUUACUGUGUUUAUUCCUCUUAAAGUUGAGCCUUCUUUCUCCACUUAAAAGUAUUCCCUUUACUUCCUUCCACCACUUGUUCUUCUAAGUAAACUCAGGGGAUAUCCUAUGAUCCACAUCAUAGAAACUGGUCAGGAUGAGAUCAUCUCAGAAGUUUCUUCUUGCAGUCUUAAUAUUUUGUGUAUCUGGGGUUGCUUUGUUUCCAGUCUUGGUGUUGACAGGAUGGCUGGGAUAUGUUUGUAAGGUCAAAACUGUUUUGUAUAAUAUUAAGUUCACAAAGUUACUGUGAACCAAGCUUGAUUGUAACUUCAUGAAUAGAGGCAGCCAGAAAGAGGGAAAAAAUUGGCUUUAUUUCUAGAACCCCCAGCCCAUAAAUUCUCUCUAGGAGGAUAUCAAACUACUGAGUAUUAUAUCAUCAGAAAAAGCAUUUGUGGGCUAGAAAGAUCUCAGGAAGUGGGGAAGCCGAUGCAGGCAGCUGUCUUUAGAAAUGAUUAAGAAAUCAAUCAUUUCAAGGGUUCCAUGAAUAGCAUGAAGUACCAUCCAAUAAUCACUUCUGUCUGCAUCAACAGCUUAAGAUUUUUUAAACUAUUAAGAUUUUGAGAUUGCAAUACUUGUUUACUCUUCAGAAGAGAAGGGACAGGUUGGGAAAAUAAUUAAGUCUUGGAUCUCAUCUAAUAACCAUUUUUUUUUUAUCCCUUGCAUACUGCAGCUUACUUUUUUGUUACAGUGUUUGCAUUUAAACGGAAACAUCAUCGUCCAGGAACAAAUGUGGUCUUUUCAUAUUAUUUGGGAGAACAGCAGGACUUCA